AUUCUUCCCAGGACCUCAGCGCAGCCCUGGCCCAGGAAGGCAGGAGACAGAGGCCAGGACGGUCCAGAGGUGUCGAAAUGUCCUGGGGACCUGAGCAGCAGCCACCAGGGAAGAGGCAGGGAGGGAGCUGAGGACCAGGCUUGGUUGUGAGAAUCCCUGAGCCCAGGCGGUAGAUGCCAGGAGGUGUCUGGACUGGCUGGGCCAUGCCUGGGCUGACCUGUCCAGCCAGGGAGAGGGUGUGAGGGCAGAUCUGGGGGUGCCCAGAUGGAAGGAGGCAGGCAUGGGGGACACCCAAGGCCCCCUGGCAGCACCAUGAACUAAGCAGGACACCUGGAGGGGAAGAACUGUGGGGACCUGGAGGCCUCCAACGACUCCUUCCUGCUUCCUGGACAGGACUAUGGCUGUGCAGGGAUCCCAGAGAAGACUUCUGGGCUCCCUCAACUCCACCCCCACAGCCAUCCCCCAGCUGGGGCUGGCUGCCAACCAGACAGGAGCCCGGUGCCUGGAGGUGUCCAUCUCUGACGGGCUCUUCCUCAGCCUGGGGCUGGUGAGCUUGGUGGAGAACGCGCUGGUGGUGGCCACCAUCGCCAAGAACCGGAACCUGCACUCACCCAUGUACUGCUUCAUCUGCUGCCUGGCCUUGUCGGACCUGCUGGUGAGCGGGAGCAACGUGCUGGAGACGGCCGUCAUCCUCCUGCUGGAGGCCGGUGCACUGGUGGCCCGGGCUGCGGUGCUGCAGCAGCUGGACAAUGUCAUUGACGUGAUCACCUGCAGCUCCAUGCUGUCCAGCCUCUGCUUCCUGGGCGCCAUCGCCGUGGACCGCUACAUCUCCAUCUUCUACGCACUGCGCUACCACAGCAUCGUGACCCUGCCGCGGGCGCGGCGAGCCGUUGCGGCCAUCUGGGUGGCCAGUGUCGUCUUCAGCACGCUCUUCAUCGCCUACUACGACCACGUGGCCGUCCUGCUGUGCCUCGUGGUCUUCUUCCUGGCUAUGCUGGUGCUCAUGGCCGUGCUGUACGUCCACAUGCUGGCCCGGGCCUGCCAGCACGCCCAGGGCAUCGCCCGGCUCCACAAGAGGCAGCGCCCGGUCCACCAGGGCUUUGGCCUUAAAGGCGCUGUCACCCUCACCAUCCUGCUGGGCAUUUUCUUCCUCUGCUGGGGCCCCUUCUUCCUGCAUCUCACACUCAUCGUCCUCUGCCCCGAGCACCCCACGUGCGGCUGCAUCUUCAAGAACUUCAACCUCUUUCUCGCCCUCAUCAUCUGCAAUGCCAUCAUCGACCCCCUCAUCUACGCCUUCCACAGCCAGGAGCUCCGCAGGACGCUCAAGGAGGUGCUGACAUGCUCCUGGUGAGCGCGGUGCACGCGGCUUUAAGUGUGCUGGGCAGAGGGAGGUGGUGAUAUUGUGUGGUCUGGUUCCUGUGUGACCCUGGGCAGUUCCUUACCUCCCUGGUCCCCGUUUGUCAAAGAGGAUGGACUAAAUGAUCUCUGAAAGUGUUGAAGCGCGGACCCUUCUGGGUCCAGGGAGGGGUCCCUGCAAAACUCCAGGCAGGACUUCUCACCAGCAGUCGUGGGGAACGGAGGAGGACAUGGGGAGGUUGUGGGGCCUCAGGCUCCGGGCACCAGGGGCCAACCUCAGGCUCCUAAAGAGACAUUUUCCGCCCACUCCUGGGACACUCCGUCUGCUCCAAUGACUGAGCAGCAUCCACCCCACCCCAUCUUUGCUGCCAGCUCUCAGGACCGUGCCCUCGUCAGCUGGGAUGUGAAGUCUCUGGGUGGAAGUGUGUGCCAAGAGCUACUCCCACAGCAGCCCCAGGAGAAGGGGCUUUGUGACCAGAAAGCUUCAUCCACAGCCUUGCAGCGGCUCCUGCAAAAGGAGGUGAAAUCCCUGCCUCAGGCCAAGGGACCAGGUUUGCAGGAGCCCCCCUAGUGGUAUGGGGCUGAGCCCUCCUGAGGGCCGGUUCUAAGGCUCAGACUGGGCACUGGGGCCUCAGCCUGCUUUCCUGCAGCAGUCGCCCAAGCAGACAGCCCUGGCAAAUGCCUGACUCAGUGACCAGUGCCUGUGAGCAUGGGGCCAGGAAAGUCUGGUAAUAAAUGUGACUCAGCAUCACCCA